GAGAAGGCCCAAAGACUCGGGCUGAACAGGCUGGCCUCUCUGGGGUUCGUGGGGCCUAAGAAUAGGAUUGCCCUGGUCAGUGUAGCUUGGAAGUCAGGGAGUGGGGGUGGAGACGCCCUCCAGGACUGACAUGGCUCCCUGUAAAUGUAAACCCCCAAACCAGAGACUCAGUUAUAGGAUACAUAUAUUAGGGAGUUUGGUAUGGUGAGUGAGCACUUAGGGUUGGGGUUCAAGUCUUGUUUCGGUUACUCUGUGACUUUGGACAAGUUUCUUAACCUCUCUGAGCAUUUAAAAAAUCUCAUCUGCAAAAUGGGAAGGGAGCUGGACCACAGUGGGACAAGGACACCUCCAGACAGGUUGCCAGGGCCCCACAUGGAGGAGGCAGGUGGGCCCAUGGCCCGGGCCAAGGCCCGAGUGGUAAGUGCCACAUUGACAUGGCGGCAGCGGCCCCCCACCCAGGAAGAGAUCAAACAUGGUUUUCACAAGGUGUCCCUGGUGUCAGGGGCCCAGAUGGAAGCCCCGCAGAAGGAGAUGUUUGAGUUCAGCCGUCGAGAGGAAGUGGAAGUCAAUGGCUUUGCAACACAGGAAGAAGAGACUGUGAAUUGCCAGGGCCCUCGGGAUACAGCUGGCUCCAAGAACUUCCAGAGCCAUGGACCCAUCUUUUCCAAGAAGUACAUACCACCUCCCAAGGAGAAAAGGCCUGAGGGGAGGCUGAAGGAGGCUGUGGACCAGAGUGAUGGCAGCCGCCAAGCUCCCAGGACUGAGCCCCCAUGUGUGGGAGCUAUGGCCAGGACUGAGCUUUUGGUUCCCCUGCCUGGGCCCCGAGAGCCAAGUCCCCACCCAGGUGUAGGUCUCACCAGUGGUAGCUCCCGGAGCCUCGAGGAAUACCGAGUGACACGCACUGUGCGGACCACCACAGUGGUGGGAGGUCAUGUGGACCGGCGGAUGAGCAGCUCUGUGACUGUGAGGCCAGUGUCCUCAGGCGAGGCCCUGCCACGGGGCCGUCAGGUCUCCCGCAUGGUGCCGCCAGUGGUGGUGGGCUCCCCACCAGGCUCGCCCAGCCGCAGCCAGGCCGUGAAAGUGCUAAGUAACCUCGUGCCUGCUGGGCACAGCCCCCCUGCCAGUCACCUGCCCAGGCCCACGGCUGGCGGGCCAAGGAGCACAGGUCUGGGCAGCACAGUGGGGGCAGCCUUGAGGCAGCUGCCUGAGACCGGGACAGCAGAGCUUAAAGACAGCUCUGCCCUGGCCUCUACAGGCAUCCCAGCCAGUGCUCACCUGCCUAAGAAUCAGGAUGCCCCUGCAGCCUGUCCGGACAGAGACCAGGGCAGAGCCCCGGAUGCCAGGGCCUGUGAGCUCUGGCAGGUGCUGGGAGCCCCCAGUUCCACUGAGCUCCCUCUCCAGACUUCUCAGGGUCAAGCAUCAGUCCCCUCCUCUCCCAGACUCGAGACCCAUGUCCCCUCUCCUGGCCUAACUCACCCUGCAAAGCAGCCUGUGGUGCCCACUCACCCCGGGGCCCGGCUCACUCCCCUUGUUCUGCCCCCUAAAAAAAAGGACGGGCCCGUGGACCCCCCUGCUGCCACCGUCCUGCCCAUGGUGAGGAGCGAGCAUGUGACAGUCCCUGGACAACCUCCUGCUCCAUCCACUACAAGAAGGAAGGAUGUCCCCAGCCCAGGAGGUCUUUCUGCUCCAUCGUCCCCAAGGAAUAAGUUUGUUCAGAACUCUGAAAAUGUCCCUGUCCUCCCCUUUACCCAGAGGGAGGUCGUGAAGGGCCCCGGUGCUCCUGCUGCCUCAUCUCCCACCCGGAAGGAGGUGGUGCAGGGGUCCAGUGCUUCUGCUGCCUCGUCCCCCACCUGGAAAGAGGUCGUGAAGGGCCCUGGUGCUCCUGCUGCCUCAUCUCCCACCCAGAAGGAGGUGGUGCAGGGGUCCAGUGCUCCUGCUGCCUUGUUCCCCACCUGGAAAGAGGUCGUGAAGGGCCCCGGUGCUCCUGAUGCCUCAUUUCCCACCUGGAAAGAGGUUGUGAAGGGCCCUGGUGCUCCUGCUGCCUCAUCCCCCACCCAGAAGGAGGUGGUGCAGGGGUCUGGUGCUCCUGCUGCCUUGUCCACCACCCCAAAAGAGGUUGUGAAGGGCCCUGGUGCUCCUGCUGCCUCAUCGCCCACCCAGAAAGAGGUUGUGAAGGGCCCCUGUGCUCCUGCUGCCUCAUCUCCCACCCAGAAGGAGGUGGUGCAGGGGUCUGGUGCUCCUGCUGCCUUGUCCCCCAAGUCAACUGAGGUUGUCCAGGGCCCAAAAGGCAGCAGUAGCAUCCAAAAAGAGGCUGUCCAGGGUAUUGCAGGCAGCCUUGCCCCGCCCCUCACCAAGGAAGAGACUGUUCAAGGCCCAAUUGCUCCUGCCACCUCACUCCCCAAACAGGAUAAGGGGGUCCAGGACUCUGAAGGGAGCCCCAUCUCAUCUCUCACCCAGAAAGAGGUUGUGCAGGACCCUGAUGCUCUCCCUGCCCCAUCUUCCUCAGUGGACAGGGUGUCCCCCAGCCCAGGAGGCACCCCUGCCCCAGUGCCAACAGGAGCAGAGGCCAGCACGGAGUCCCAGCUUGUCUCUGAUCCCACCGAGGGCAAGACGUGCACAGAGACAUCAAGGGAGGAGGAUGAGGUGGCCCUGGCCGCUGACCUGGAGAUAUUCCUGGAUACGCUGCGGAGCAUGGAGCCCCCUGAGAUCCUCCGCACUCACCGGCUGCCACGAGCCCCUCGCUCCUCCUACCUGUCCAUGUACGCCACGCUGCCUGCCAUUGAGGAGGACCAGCUGGGGCCAUGGGUGCUGGGCCCCGGACCCCAGGAGGUGCCUUCACUGGAAGAGAAAGAGGAGGAGGAGGAGGAGGAACCAGAGAACCCCUAUCUGAGUGACGAUGAGAAGCUCCAGCGCAGGCAGGAGAAAGCUGGGCCCAGCCCCUCCAGGGACCUCCACCCUGCCAGACCCACCCAGGUCUCCUGCUCUCCUCUGGAGAUGAUGAAGAAGCAUGUAGCAGGAACCAAGGGCCCCCACUCAGAGCUGGGAUUGGAACUGCAGGGAGGCAGCAGGCCCACUUCCCGUCUUGGAGGCAGCCUUCUGUUCGGCAGUCUGGUGCCUACCGCCAAGGAGGCCUCCACCCCGGAACCGCUGGGCACAAAACUAUCUGCUCUGCUGCCCCAUGGGGCACCGGGGCUCAGGAAGGUGCCAGGACAGUUGCCCCUGCUUUGCAGUGAAAGAUCAUCCCCAACGGAGAAGCUUGCCUGUUCCCUGCCCCUGGAGGGGUGGAGCCCAGCCUUAAAGACCCAGGGCAAGCUGAACACCAGGCCUGGAAAGGUGAUCUUCUUCUCAGAGUCUGGCUGCCAAGGCAGUGGCAGGGAGGUCUGGGGAGACAUCGUUGAUGCCUCAGGCUGGGCCCCCGUAGCCUCCAUAAGGGUAGUUCGAGGCUGCUGGGUGCUGUACGAAGAGCCAGAGUUCCGGGGUCAGAAGCUGGUCCUGCCUGAAGGAGACAUGGAACUCAGAACCCCAGGGACAAAGUGGAGUCCCCAAGGCAUCGGCUCCCUAAGGAGGGUUGUCUGGGACUACAGCACCCCGGAAAUCAGCCUCUUCUCUGAGGAGGGCCUCAAGGGGGAGCAAGUGAAGCUAACAGAGGCCUUGAAGAAUUCCCAGGGUCUGGAGAAGCCCCUGCAGGUGGCAUCUGCCACCGUCUCUGCAGGACUGUGGCUACUGUACCCCAAACCAUUAUUCGAAGACACUCCCUACAUCCUGGAACCUGGAGAGUACCCCACCUCAGAGGCCUGGGGCACAUCGGACCCCAGCGUGGGCUCCCUGAAGCCCAUGAGAUUGGGCUGCCCAAGUGUGGAGAAGCCAGGGGAGCCCAGGGCUGUGGUGUAUGAGGCCCCAGGCUUUCAGGGCCGCAGCUGGGAAGUGAGCCGAGACAUCUACAACCUUCAGCAGCCAGAGGACAGCCAGAGCCCCCACCUGGCCUCUGUGGGGUCCCUGAGAGUUCUCGGAGGCUGCUGGGUGGGCUACGAGAAGGAGGGCUUCCGGGGCCACCAGUAUCUGCUGGAGGAGGGGGAAUACCCAGACUGGUCACACUGGGGAGGCUAUGACGAGUUGCUGACCUCCCUCCGGGUCAUCCGGACGGACUUCGGGGACCCGGCCGUCGUGCUAUUUGAGGCCAUGGACUUCGAGGGGCACGGCGUGGAGGUGAGCAAGGCAUUGCCGGAUGUGGAGCUGGUGCAACACGGCCCCAGCACACAGGCCAUCCACGUGCUCAGCGGCGUGUGGGUGGCCUACCAGGAGGUGGGCUUCUCCGGGGAACAGUACGUGCUGGAGAAGGGCGUGUAUCGUAACUGCGAGGACUGGGGCGCUGGCAACAGCACCCUCGCCUCGCUGCAGCCGGUCCUACAGGUCGGGGAGCACGAUCUGCACUUCGUCUCAAAGAUUCAGCUUUUCUCCCGCCCCGACUUUCUGGGCGACCACUUCUCUUUCGAAGAUGACCAGGCCGCUCUGCCCGCCUCCUUCCGACCUCAGUCCUGCCGGGUCCACGGCGGCAGCUGGAUCCUGUUUGAUGAGACGAACUUCGAGGGUGACCAGCACAUUCUCUCUGAGGGCGAGUUCCCCACUCUCACGGCCAUGGGCUGCCUCGCCUCCACAGUCCUGGGCUCUCUCCAGAAGGUAUCCCUGCACUUUUCAGAGCCUUCCAUUUUCCUGUAUGGACUCGAGUGCUUCGAGGGGAAGGAGAUCGAGCUCAGCAGGGAGGUGCGGAGCCUGCAAGCCGAGGGCUUCAACAACCAUGUGCUGUCUGUGCGGAUCAAGGGGGGCAUUUGGGUGCUAUGUGAACACAGUGACUUCCGGGGCCGCCAGUGGCUGGUGGGAAGCUGCGAGAUCACCAACUGGCUGACCUACAGCGGCACCCAGAGGGUGGGCUCCCUCUACCCCAUCAAGCAGCGCCGGGUUUAUUUCCGCCUCUGGAAUGCAGCACUGGGGGGAUUCCUGGCAGUGCCGGACCAUGUGGAGGACAUGAAAGCAGGCCGUGUGGUGGUCGCCGACCCCCAAGCUGGAGGUAGCUGCAUCUGGUACUACGAGGAUGGGCUGCUGAAGAACCAGAUGGCCCCCACCAUGAGCCUACAGGUGAUUGGACCCCCUAGCCCAGGCUCCAAGGUGGUGCUGUGGGCCGAGAGCCGCCUGCCGCGCCAGACGUGGAGCAUCAGUGAAUCGGGCCACAUCUGCAGCCAGAUGUUCGAAGGCCAGAUCCUGGACGUGAAGGGAGGCCGGGGCUACGACCGGGACCACGUGGUGCUAUGGGAGCCGGAUGAGGACAGGGCAUCCCAGAUCUGGACUAUCCACGUGCUUUGAAACUUUUCCCCUCACCCUCCAGCCCUGGAGGCUUUUGCUGGGAUGAAUGUUUUUAUAGGGUUUUUGUUGUAACAUAAGCUAUUUUCUAAUAUGCUGCCAGGUA